GACGUUGCCUGUGGGUGCCCGCGAACCAACGGUUAGCGGUGGCAGGGGCUGACUGAGAGCGUCUGCUUGAAAAUGGAUCCUCACUUCUUCACUUGGAUAUAAUAAUAUAGACUGCCGACAUUCUGGGAACUGAUCAGUCUUCCAGCUUCCAGUGUGGUGCCCUCCCUCAAUUGUGCUGAGUGUCCCCCAAUCCAGAGAUAUUCUGUAAUUUCUUCCUCAGAAAGAAACAAAACAAAAUUCUGAUCUUCCCAGAUGAAGACAGAGUCUUUCUCUGUCACCCAGGCUGGAGUACAGUGGCACGAUCUCGGCUCCCUGCAACGUCCGCCUCCCGAGUUCAAGUGAUUCUCCUGCCUCAGCCACCCGAGUAGCUGGGUCUACAGGUGUGCGCCACCAUGCCUGGCUAAUUUUUGUAUUUUUAAGAGAGACGGGGUUUCACCAUGCUGGCCAGGCUGGUCUCGAACUCCUGACCUCGUGAUCCGCCUGCCUCAGCCCCUCAAAGUGCUAGGAUUAGAGAUAAUGGAUUCUGAAUUAAUGCAUAGUAUAGUAGGAAGCUAUCAUAAACCUCCAGAAAGAGUAUUUGUUCCCUCAUUCACCCAGAAUGAACCAUCUCAGAAUUGCCAUCCUGCAAACUUAGAAGUUACCUCUCCUAAGAUACUUCAUAGCCCAAAUAGCCAAGCUCUUAUUUUAGCCUUAAAAACUCUUCAGGAAAAAAUUCAUCGUUUAGAGCUGGAGAGAACACAAGCUGAAGAUAACCUGAACAUUCUUUCCAGAGAAGCAGCACAGUAUAAGAAGGCCUUAGAGAAUGAAACAAAUGAGAGAAAUCUGGCACACCAGGAGCUGAUAAAGCAGAAAAAAGAUAUAAGUAUACAGUUAAGCUCAGCCCAGUCUCGUUGUACUCUUCUAGAGAAGCAACUAGAAUAUACAAAGAGAAUGGUUCUCAACGUAGAGCGAGAAAAGAACAUGAUCCUAGAACAACAGGCCCAGCUUCAGAGGGAAAAAGAACAAGAUCAGAUGAAGCUGUAUGCAAAACUUGAAAAGCUUGAUGUCUUAGAAAAAGAGUGUUUCAGACUUACAACAACUCAGAAAACUGCUGAGGACAAGAUUAAACAUUUAGAAGAAAAACUUAAGGAAGAAGAACAUCAGCGUAAGCUAUUUCAAGACAAAGCUUCUGAGCUUCAAACUGGACUUGAAAUCAGUAAAAUUAUAAUGUCUUCAGUUUCAAAUCUAAAGCACUCCAAGGAAAAGAAGAAAUCUUCAAAGAAAACUAAAUGUAUAAAGAGACGACCACCUUGGCAAAUUUGUUCAAAGUUUGGAGCACUGCCUUUUGUGGCUGAAAAGGUGAGAGGGGAUAAAAUGAAGAUAGUCGUUCAAAAAAACUCCUGUUUUGUUAUGAGGCAACAUCGUGACCCACAUAUCCUUCAGAAACCUUUUAACGUGACUGAGACUAGAUGUCUCCCCAAGCCUUCUAGAACAACUUCCUGGUGUAAAGCUAUUCCUCCUGACUCAGAAAAGUCCAUUUCCAUUUGUGACAAUUUAUCUGAACUUUUGAUGGCAAUGCAAGAUGAGCUGGACCAAAUGAGCAUGGAGCACCAAGAACUACUGAAACAAAUGAAGGAAACUGAAAGUCAUUCAGUCUGUGACGACAUAGAAUGUGAACUAGAGUGUUUACUCAAGAAAAUGGAAAUUAAAGGAGAACAAAUCUCCAAACUGAAGAAGCAUCAAGACAGUGUCUGUAAACUGCAGCAAAAAGUUCAAAACUCAAAGAUGAGUGAAGCUUCAGGUAUUCAGCAAGAAGACAGCUACCCUAAAGGAUCAAAGAACAUAAAAAAUAGCCCCAGAAAAUGUUUGACUGACACUAACCUUUUUCAGAAAAACAGCAGCUUUCAUCCAAUACGAGUUCAUAAUCUUCAAAUGAAAUUGAGAAGAGAUGAUAUCAUGUGGGAACAGUAACAAAACAGCAAAACUGUCACCUUAAUGAACUUUGUCAGUGAGACCUUGAAUUGUCUAAAGUGGUUUUAAUUUAAUAUAACUUUGUGACAUUUUGAAUCAUGUUUCUAGUUUCUAUAAAACAUGAAGUUGCAGUAUUUAAAAAUUAAUGCCUAAUGACCUGGUGGGUUCCAAAUAAUAAAUUAAUUGCUUUUUUAUUUUUCUUAUUGAUUGAAGCCCGUAACCUCAUCUUGUCUUAGAAACAUUGUUGGCUUUGCAGAUAUCUUAAGCUAAAUUUAAGAAAUUGUACUAGAUUGACAAUAUUCAAAAUUGAGUUAAAUCCAAGCUACAAGUACCAUUCAUUCCACUUUUCAUUUAGUAGGUUUGGAACCUUAAAAACCAAUGUUCAAUGAACAGAGUUCAGAAAGAUCAUUUAGCUUUCCUGGUGCCUUCUUUCUAUUUUGUUUUAGAGCUGUGAAAUGUUUUUCUCUUUUGGAAAAGGAAAAACUUAAUAGUUACACAGUUUUGUGAAGAAGCCUUUAAUCCAAGUUUUAUGAGACAGUAGGAACCUAUAGCUACUUAAUUUUUAGGAGACAGUAAUUCAGUUGCAGAAGCUUUCCUCUGCUAUUCCCAUUCUCUUUUACAAAACUAGUUUUUUUUAAAAAAUCAAUGAUCAAUUUUAUCUUACUACUUUAUAACUUUUGCUGACUUUUAUUCUUUGCAUUGUAUGUAAUGUCCAUCAGUAUAAAUUGAGACUGUGAAUUUCUAGGACCCACAAAAGUGGUAUUUUUUUUUUGUACAAGAAAGUAUAGAGGAAGAGGAAGCUGGGCAUUAAAUUACCUCAUCCAGCAGAAAUUCACGGUAGUAUGGUAUAUUUUUAUUUUUUAUAUUUUAAAAUCAAUAAUGUCAAAUGUCAUUGUGUAUGCAUGCUUUAUAAUAAAUUUACACUUGAUCAUUUUUCUGGAAGCCUAUGGGAACUAGUACAACUCUUCUGAACUCUUGGUUUCUCACUCAAAUCCUCUGAGGCAACUGGGGAACUAGAGUCAUGAACUGAAUUAGAAAUAGAGGACAGAGAGAAAAGAUAUAAUAGAAUGGAGGAGCUCAAAUAUAGGGUAGCAGUUUAAGAGAUGGUGAUUCCUAAGGGACAGAGUUGGAAGUACAUAUUUACUGAAUUCUUUGAACCCACAGCUGAUGGAAUGUUCAAGCUAUAGAUGUGAAAGAAUUUUUAGGUCAGGAUCUUGGGAAGCUAAGGAGAGCAAUUUUUAAAAGACAGUUUUUCUGUUUUCCUAGGAAAUUCCCAAGAAGCUUGUGUAGGAAAAAGUUGGUAAUUAUGGAUCUUUUGGGGAGGAAGAGAACUAUAAUUCAUUCUAAUGGUGAGGAGAGAUACCAUGUUAGAAUACCUUCCAUACCUGGAAGUGGGGAAGUGACUGAAGAUGGGCACAUUGAUGCUUGAAAUUGUCCUUGAAAGUAGUUAAUGGCAGAGAUCAAAAUUUCCUCCUGUUGUAAAUAGUGCAUGUGCCCUUUGCCAGCUUUCACUCCCACUCAUUCACACCCUUAGCUCCUCAGCCCUGGAGAUGUUCCAUAGGGUGUUUGAUCUAAACUCAGUUGCAUCACCUUACCUGUUUUUCUACUUUGCCUUUCCUCCUUGAGGAUAUGAGUUUUAUAGCUUAAGCUUAGCUUUUUGCUAAACUUUUUAGCUUUCUGCUAUCCACCAGGACCAUAAUGCAGACCUAUAGUUCUGUGCCUUUGUUUUCUAUACAUUUAGGAAGGUGGCUGAAUAUAUUUAGUUAUUAAUAAUUCAUUACUUGUGAAAAGGUAUUGCUUUAAAAAUUAUCAUUAAAAAUUUAAAAACCGUCCAGGCGCGGUGGCUCACACCUAUAAUCCCAGCACUUUGGGAGGCCGAGGCAGGCAGAUCACGAGGUCAGGAGAUUGAGACCAUCCUGGCCAACAUGUGAAACCCUGUCUCUACUAAAUUACAAAAAUUAGCCGGGUGUGGUGGCGCAUGCCUGUAAUCCCAGCUACUUGGGAGACUGAGGCAGGGGAAUCGCUUGAACCUGGGAGAUGGAGGUUGCAGUGAGCUGAGAUCUCACCACUGUACUCCAGCCUGGUGACACAGCAAGACUCUGUCUCAAAAAAAAAAAAAAAAAUUAAAACCAUUUUAGGAACAUGGAAUAUUUCAACUGAGAAUUUUCUUAAAAAUUAGUCCAGUGUAGUAGAAAAAACCACAACUUCAGAGCUAGGAAACUUGGUUUCAAAUUCUGGGACUCUACCAUUUAAUAGCUUGGACAAGUCAGAUAACUUUCUGGAGCCUCAGUUUCUCAUCUGUAAAGUGAGGAUUAUACUAAUAUCUCCCUCACAGGACUAUACUAAUUUGUUGUGAGGAGUUAAUGAAAUAACAUGGGAAAGCACCCAGCAGAAGAGUUGACACUUAUUAAACACUCAAUAAAUAUUUUUUGAAUCUGAGUGGCAAAAAAAAAAAAAAAAUGUAGAACACAUGUUUGCAUGGGUUGAAGCCUAAAAGCAAACACCUAAAUAUAUUAUUGGUAAAAGUGGGAAUAUUCUCACUUAUUUUGGUUUUUAUCUCUUUCUGUGUGCCUGAAGGGAAAUGGCUUUGUCAUCUUUCCUAGCCCAGGUUUCUAAUGGGAGGGGGUAAAGAACACAGUCCUGUCAUUGUGCUGAAACAUGUAACCACACACAGCAAAUAGGUUUGGAGUAUGGUGUGGUUGUUGAGGUGACAUUUAUUAUUGAGAGACAAUGAAGAAUGGUGUCUUGUUGCUUCAUCACAGCUACUGAACUCACAGACUGCCUGCUUGCCAGAGCCUUUGACUCCUCAGGGGGUGGAGCAAAAGAUUUCUUUCCUGGAUGGAGCAGUCAGUCUAUGGUCAGUGUAAGAGUUGCUGUAGCAACCUCACAGCUGUGCUCUGUCUAGCAGAAACUUGGUAUGAUUUCACGGAUUUUGUUCACUUAAGUAAAAAACAGAUUUGUUUGGUUUUUAUGUAAUUAGAAAUUGAAAUAAUGGAAUUGGAAUUUUCUAGCCAAGGCAGGUCUCAAUUUUGAUGAAACUGAAGCCAGAAAGUUCCAGUGUUUGAAGCAGCAGGUAUUGUGACUAUAUUCUGAUACUGGAAAUGGGAGUUGGAAUCCUGAAUUAACUGUACUUGGGUGGAUCAUUGGCAACCCAGCCAUUUUUAUUAGGUUGUAGAUAAAGACAGGAGGGUCAGAGGGAAAUGUUCAGUUUUCAACAAUGUAAGAUUAAAGUGGGAGAUACUUAGUACAUAGUAAGUUAACUGGCUGGGAUAAUGUAGAUAAUGUACUUGAAAAUUAUUUUUGAGCUUUUUUGGUAGCUUUCUUACUUUAUUCCUUUUUUUCUAUACCUGCCAGUAGAUGUGAGAGCUUUUCUUACUUUAAAAGUGUAAUUUUAACUAUAAAUGUAUAUUCUUUUUUUUUUUUUUUUGGUGGGCAUGGAGUCUCGCUGUGUCACCCAGGCUAGAGUGCAGUGGCACGAUCUCAGCUCACUGCAACCUCCACCUCUCAGGUUCAAGCUAUUCUCCUGCCUCAGCCUCCCGAGUAGCUGGAAUUACAGGCACCUGCCAUACACCCAGCUAAUUUUUGUAUUUUUAGUAGAGAUGGGGUUUCACUGUGUUAGCCAGGAUGGUCUGGAUCUCCUGACCUCAGGUGAUCCGCCCACCUCAGCCUCCCAAAGUGCUGGGAUUACAGGCAUGAGCCACUGCGCCCAGCCUAAAUGUGUAUUCUUAUCCAUGAUAAGAGAUCAAAAAUUAAAUAAAAAUUUUACUUGUAAUGUGAGAAAUCAAUCUAAGGGGGGAAGAGGCCAGUUGGUUAUGCACAAUGGAAGGAGUGCAUUGUGGACAGAAAUGCAACAGCUGCCAUUAUUGGUGUAGAGUAAAUAAUGAAACUCCUAAUGGGGUUUCCUGGAACAAUAUUCAGCUGUAACUAAAGCUUUAUCUACUGAGAACAUUUAAUUGUAGGUGACGUGUAGAUAAGUAUAAGCUGACACUCAGACAUAUGACAAGACAACCUUCACUAAGGCAUAAUAGCAACUGUGAGAUUUUUAAAAAACUAUGCGUGCCAUUGCACCUUUUAAUUAAAGUGAGAUGAGGAUAAAUAAAAAUAAUAUUGACUGUCACUCAUCUGAAAAUAAAUUUACUUCUUGGUAAUUAAAUAGACCUUCUCAAUGCCUCAGCCUUUUUCUUCAUAUUCCAUCUACUUGUUUUCAUGUAACUUUGUCUUUCAAUUCGUUUUUGUUUUUUUUUUCCUGUAAGGAGAAUUAGACAUAGAAAAAUUAUAAAUUUAAGCCUUAAAAUAAUGUCUGGGCCAGAGUUUGUUGUUACUUUUGCUGUAGAUUGUUUACUUAAAGAAUUAGGUGAAUUUUUUUUUUCCUGGUAGGUUUAUUGGGAGUGUUCUCCAUAUUGAUAUAGAUGGAUCCAUUUCCCAUUUGGGGCUGAGCACUGUGUCUUACGCCUGUAAUCCCAGCACUGUGAGAGGCCGAGGCAGGCGGAUCACCUAAGUCAGGAGUUCAACACCAGCCUGGCCAAUGUAGUGAAACCCUGUCUCUACUAAAAAUAAAAAAAAAUUAGCUGGGUGUGGUAGCAUGCAGUCCAGCUACUCGGGAGGCUGAGGCAGGAUAAUUGCUUGAACCUGGGAGGCAGAGGUUGCGGUGAGCCGAGAUUGUGCCACUGCACUCCAGCCUGGGCAACAGAGCAAGACUCUGCCUCAAAGCAAAAAAAAAAAGAAAAGAAAAGAAAAAAGGAAUAGCCCAGUAUUGUUUGUUUGGGGAGGGGCAGGGUGUGGUUCCACCAACUGUGGGCACCAGAAUGGUGCUUUCUUUGAUACUAUGCUAAGAGGAAGAGGUUUGAGAGCCAAGAGUUCUUUAUUUGGAUAUUGGUAUGUUUGACUUGUUCAUCAGUGAGUAUUUAUUGAUCUCUAAUUAUUGAUCUCAAAAUACUGUAUUAGCUACUAUGGAAUUCCGUUUUCAAGUUGCUUAUAGUCUUGAGGAGAGAUAAGAUGUAUAUAUAUUUAAAAGGAAGAAAACAGUAAGUGACAUGAAAGGCAUAAUGACAACCACAGAGCAGAUGCUCAAAUAUUUAUUUGCCUACUAAAUGUUUGUUCUCAUCUAUCGAUAAAGUGCUUAAGAAGUUGGCCUGUUUGUAAUUUCUUCAUUUUCUAUCUAUCUUGAUUUAUAUACCUUCACCUUUUUAAAUUUUUUGCCUGGUAGCAGUAUUGGUCUAGGAUUUUCACUCUUUAUUAGGCUUCUUGAUUGAAGAUACCAGUUCCUUUAGUAAUUUCAAAAUGCCGGCCAUAGCCAGUCUAUAAUCCAAUUCAAAGGCAUGAGUGGAAAAAGUGGGUAUGAAACAAUGAAGUAAAUGGAGAAGUGGGGGAAAAUCAAGCAAUAAUCACUUAGACUAAAACAGAACAAUAAGAAUUAUACAGAAAGGUUAUAUUCUAGAGGCCAAGUAUUGACUUGCACAGAAUUGUGUAAAUGAUUGCCAUUCACUUCCCUUAUGAACUUAAGCCACUCAAUUUCUGCAUACUUCAGCCUCCUCAUUGGUUGGAUCCAGUCAGUGUUUUUCAUAGUACAUACAGUCAUACCGGUGGAUUGUCAAAUCAAUUUAGCGGGUCACUACCAGCAUUUUUUUUUUUUUUUUUUUUUUGAGAUUGGAGUCUCGCUCCUUCACCCAGGCUGGAGUGCAAUGGUACAAUCUCGUCUCACUGCAACCUCCACCUCCCAGGUUCAAGCAAUUCUCCUGCCUCAGCCUCCCAAGUAGCUGGGAUUAUAGGUGUGCACCACCAUGCCCUGCUAAUUUUUUGUAUUUUAGUAGAGAUGGGGUUUCACUGUAUUGCCCAGGCUGGUCACGAACUCCUGAGCUCAGGCAAUCUGCCCGCCUCAGUGUCCCAAAGUGCUGGGAUUACAGGCGUGAGCCACCAUGCCUGGCCAGCAUUUUUUAAAUGAUAUAAAAUAGUAUUGAAAAUAUCAGAAUGUGGCCAGGUGCGAUGGCUCACGCCUGUAAAAUCUUAACACUUUAGGAGGCCGAGGCGGGCAGAUUGCCUGAGCUCAGGAGUUCAAGACCACCCUGGGCGACAUGGUGAAAUCCCAUCUCUACUAAAAAUACAAAAAUUAGCCGGGCAUGGUGGUAUGUGCCUGUAAUCCCGGGUACUCGGGAGGCUAAGGCCAGAGGAUUGCUUGAACCAGGGAGGCGGAGGUUGCAGUAAGCUGAGAUUGUGCCACUGCACUCUAGCCUGAGCAGCAGAGUGAGGCUCCAUCAGCAAAAAAAAAAAAAAAAAAAAAGAUCAGAGUGCAUCACACAUAAUUAAGGUAGCUUAUGUUUUGUGAAACUUUGUGAGUACGGGUUGUCAUUUUUAAUGUAGCCCUAAAUGUUUUUUAGGGAAGAAAAAGUUGGCUUUUAAUAAGUAUUCAGUGAGAAUGAAUUUGAAGGGUGUGGAGAAAAGUGGAAUAGCCAAUUUAAAAUAGGAAUACUCCCAAGUCCCCUGUUAUGGAUGUGCCAAUCUAUUGUUUAUCCCAGAAAUAUUGUUUCAUGUGUUUUACAGAUAACAAGUCUCAUUUUAAUCAAUACUGUUGCAUUUCCUGGUCUAUAGAAUACAAUUUUCAAACACUAGCCAACUUACCUUAGAGAAAUACUGGUUUUCUAAUGUGGGCAAAUAAAUACAUUCAGUAUGAAUCCCUUAACAAAAUGACCUCAUUAUGCUACCUCUUGGUAAAAUCUAACCAAGCAUGAGUCUUAUGAUUAAGAAAGAAAUUUGCUCUGUAGGUGCUUCAGACAGUUUUACAACCAAUAAGAAUGUGAGAUUUGUCGGAGAAAAACUAUCUGCAUGUCUCCAAUCUGAAGAGAGCAAAGAUCUGUUAUUUGACAAACCCUAUUUUUCCGAGCAUCAACAGUCAGUGGCACCAUGAAAAUUAAAAACCUGAUAAUACCACCAAUGUAGUACUCUUUAAAAACAUGUCAUCUUACUCAGCAAUCAACCUGAUUGAAUAUUUUAAAAUGAAUAAGUGGAUAAAUAUCUUACCUGAAAGAUAGCUUCAUUAAAUAAACUAACUCCUGAGAGGAUUUCUUUGGCCUUUAAUAUCCUAUUUAAUAGAUUUCUUAUAACCAUAUCAGCAAAGCCACUCUGCUCUGGACAAUGGUCAGAAGGUAGGAAGAAGUGUUAUAGGGUAAUGAGCAAUAAUAAGGCCACCAAAUAUAAUCCCAUUGUAAUGGGAUUCUACCCACUUGUAGAAGUUUAUUCACCACUACAAAUUACUAAAGUUAACCUAAACAAUUAAAGAAAGAAAUCUUAGUCUUUAAGAACAGAGGAUUGUAAAGUGAGCCAGACCUUCCAAUCAGCUAAAAUAAUGUAAAAUAAUGUACUUUUCAACCUGACUUGGCUUAAUGUAGUUAAGUAAAUUUUAGGAUAGGUUCUAAAAAACCUUGAGAGGCAUUUUGUUGUUGUUGUUGUUGUUGUUAGUUUGCCUUAAAGUUAAAUGUACAUUGACCUUUGGUAUUUCUUAGAAAAACCUGUUACUGAACCUAGUACAGAAUGUGAAUCAUUUCAUGCCUGAAAUACAAGAUUGAUGUUUACAGGGCAAUUGUCCAGAAUCUUGCUGAAUUGGAAAGUAUUUCACUCUUCAUCACUGUAGAUCCGUUUAACUUUACAAAUGUGUUAUUUAAAACAUAAACCAUUUUGGUGCACAGGAAACCCACUUAAAAUUAAAUUUUAAAAAGCUCUCGAGAAGUCUGUGGAACAUUUAUGGUUUUAUAACUUACAAUUUCUAGCAAAAGUAUCUUUAAUAUCUUACAAAAUAUUUUCAGAGAUAGCUUAUCCAAAAUAUGUAAUACAUGUGAGAGAAUAGCACUGUUGAAAUGCUUGAACACAUAAAAAGCAUUAUUGCCUUCAUUUUCCCUGAAAUGAACCAAGCUACCAAUUUAAAGCUGGGAAAGUCAGUACCAGAGUUAAAAACAAGUUACUUUAAAGAUAUCUGCUUUUACUUUAAUCUAAAAAAUAAUUGAUUUUUUAAAAAACUUAUUCUAUUUUAUGUAUAUAACUUCUCCUUUAUAAGCUUAGAAAAAUUUAUAUCAGUAUUACAUUCUUGAUUCUCUCAAGGUAUGAUUUAAAUGGUGGACACUUAAGCCAAAAUUUCAAACAGGUUCUUUUUUCUUUGUUCUUUUACAGAAUGGCUCUCAAGUCGAAAGAGGGCUGUGCCUUUGGUGUUUGGGUAUGAUAUAUUUGCCUGUGAUUUCUCAUUCUCAGAGCAUUCCCAUAAAUAAUGCCACAAAGUAGAGUUUGAUUUUUUUUUUUUUGAGACGGAGUUUCGCUCUUGUUGCCCAAGCUGGAGUGCAAUGGCGCGAUCUCAGCUCACUGCAACCUCCGCCUCCCAGGUUCAAGCGAUUCUUCUGCCUCAGCCUCCCAAGUAGCUGGGAUUACAGGCAUGCGUCACCACACCCGGCUGUUUUUUUUUUUCGCAUUUUUAAUAGAAACGGGGUUUCACCGUGUUAGCCAGGCUGGUCUCGAACUCCUGACCUUAGGUGAACUGCCCGCCUCAGCCUCCCAAAGUGCUGGGAUUACAGGUGUGAGCCACCGCGCCCUGCCUAGAGUUUGAUUCUCUUAAACCGUUCUACUAAAAUACUAUCAGUUUAAACUACCAUCUACAGAAAUAAAAAACAUAAACCACUAAAAGAUUAAAGCAUUUAGGAGUUUAUAUGCAAAGAAGUCUUGCAAGGGAGUACAAGCUUUAGGAGGACAGGCUUAUCAAAUUAAAAAAUGAAAAAACCUACAAAAUUACCAAAGUCACCAAGUUUAGUUAUUCUUUUCAUGGUGGAAAACAGUUUCCUCAGAUAAUCAUCAUAUCAGAGGUCAUCAUGUAUCCUUAGAUAUCAGCAUUGCCAAGACCAGGGAUAUAGUUAUUAGUAAUUUACAGGAAAGGCUCAAGGUUUCAUUUACAUGGGAAAUGAGAACUAGACAGUGUGGUGACUGUUUUUGUUGUUAACCUUACCUCAGUGUUUUAUCUCGGGUGGUCCCCAAGACCACCUUCAGGAUCAGUGAUUCACUGGAGGGACUCACAGAACUCAGAAAAGCUGUUAAGUUAUGGUUAUGGUAUAUUAUAGCAAAAGAAUAUAUAUUAAAAUCAGCAGCUGAAAAAAGGCACAUAGGGCAAAGUCUGGGGGACACCAGGCACAAGCUUCCAGUUGUCCUUCACCUGUGAAGUCAUGUAGACAGACCAUAAUUCUCUCAGCAGACAGACCAUAAUUCUCUCAGCAACAAUGUGUGACAACAUUCUUGGAGAAUUGCUAACCAGGGAAGCUCCACCAAGCCUUGGUGUCCAGAUUUUUUCUUGAGGGUUGGUCACGUAGGCAUAGCAUGACUGAUAGCCCAUGUGGCUGACCUUCAGUUUUCAGCCCCUCCAAAGAUGGAGCUGAUACUACAUGGCCUAAGGACUUCACCAUUAAUCACAUUGUUAGCUUAGACUACCUGGUAUGGCCUAAGGCCCCCAAGUAAAUUAAAACAUUCAUAUCAGGCAGGAUAGUCCAAGGACUUAGAGGUUAUCUUGAAUCUGGACACAGGACAAACAUUUCUUUGGAAUGUGAAAAGUUUACACAAUCAAGACUUGCUAUGUUGAUCCUUUACUGCGGUAUUGUUUUUUGUUUUCUGACCCAAAAGUGAUGUGCAUUGCUUACCUAUCAUGGCCUCUGGUUAAGGUGUCAGUCUUGCCUCCAAAUUUCCUCCUAAAGCAUGGAAUUGGCCAUAAAUUUGCUUAGUGAUUUUCUGAUUUAGUAUCAUUAGUUUGAUGACUAGUUUUAUUAUGUGAGUGUGAUAAAAGGUUACGCUUAGUAUACAAAGACCUUCUUAUAAGUCUAGUUAAUAAAACUAGGGCCAUGUGUUACUACAACAUAGGAGUUAACUUUGUCUGGAGGCUUUUUCAAGCCCAAGAGGUUGUCAUUUCUUUAUGUGUAAGAUACUGCCCACAUACUAUACUGAAGUCAGGAACCAAGAACCGGUCAAUUUACCUCAGCCAAGUUGCUUGGACUGCUUUGCUUAAUAAUGGGUUUGCCAUAUCUACUUUAAUGAGAUGUGUGGCAUGGUGAUGGUUACAAAAGUGAUUUGUUAAUUAUUGCCUGGUAGGAAGGAGAACAUGUUUUUUUUGAACCUAUGCAAAUAGCCACAUGUCUGUGAAAAGUAAAGGGAUACUUUUGUGUAAUAUUUAACCAUGUAUACCAUUGUUUGUGUACUUUUUAAUUGUGUCAUUUUCUACAGUAUUAUUUUUGCAUUUUCCUGACACUGUAUUACUUACAAGUUAUAUUAAUAAUUUUUAUUAAUUUUUUUCCUGAAUCCUAAAAGGUCAGUUGGAACAUGAGACCAUUUAAAGAAUAUUAUUUCCUUCCAGUUUAUUCAAGGGUGGCCUAUUGAGAGUUUGAGAUAAAGAAGAAAGGAAUCUUUCCUUUCCUUCCCCCUCAGCCCGCCCCCUACCUUUCUUUUUUUUUUUUUUUUCUUUUCAGGGUCUUGUUCUGUCACCCAGGCUGGAGUGGAGUGAAUGCAAUCAAAGCUCACUGCAACCUCAAACUCUUGGGCUUAAGCAGUCCUCCUGCCUCUGCCUCCCAAGUAGCUGGGACUACAGGUGCAUGCCACCACACCUGGCUAAUUAAAAAAAAAAAAAAAUUUUUUUUUUUGAGGAGACGCGGUCUCACUUUGCUGCCCAGGCUGGUCUCAAACUCUGGGCUCAAGCAAUCCUUCCACCUCAGCCUCCCAAAGCUCUGGGAUUACAGGCAUGAGCCACUGUGCCCGGCAGAAUUUUUCUGUGUCCAUUAGAAAUAGAAAUCAGUCACAUGCUAUGAUUUCAAUAUGUCACUCAAAAGCCAUGUGUUGGGGCUGAACGUAGUGGCUCACGCCUAUAAUCCCAGCACUUUGGGAGGCAAAGGAAGGUGGAUCACUUGAGGUCAGGAGUUUGAGACCAGCCUCCAACAUGGUGAAACCCCGUCUCUACUAAAAAAAAAAAAAAAAUUAGCUGGGUGUGGUGGCAUGCACCUGUAGUCUCAGCUACUCAUCAGGCUGAGGCAGGAGAAUCGCUUGAACCCAGGAGACAGAGGGUGCAGUGAGCCGAGAUCAUGCCAUUGCACUCCAGCCUGAGCCAUAGAGUGAGUCUUGGUCUCAAAAAAAAAAAAAAACCUUGUGUUGGAAACCAUCUCCAAUGAAGCAGUGUUAGGAGAUAGGGCCUAAUGGAUAUAAAUUACAGUGUCUAAGAUGGAUACUUUACUCUUUUCUUUUGAGAAGGGAGAGAGUAUGUUAUGCACUGAGAACUUUUCAGAUUUCUUGCAGAGGUCAUAAUGUUCCAGACAAGCUGGCAGCAAUCAUUCCCAUCCCAUCACAGAUCCAGGCUUAUUUGUAGAAUGGUUACACAAACCAAGCAAAACCUUCUGUAAAGUUUCUACCCUUUGCUCUAAAGUUACAUAAAAACAAUUUCCAAGUUUG